GCCAUUUUCUCGAGCCGCCUGUUUCGGGUGCCGCCAUGUUGGUGAGGAGAAAUCACCGUUACGGCCACUGUCCAAAUCCCCGCGUCGCUGCACGCCGCCCGCCCGCUCCCACGCCACAGCCACCGGCGGCGAAUAGAGACUAGAGCGGCAGCGCCGGCAGCGCGGGGCCGUUGCCCAGUGUUUGCAGUUAGAGCCCCAUCUCUCUGGCGUGGUUGUUAAUAGACUGGAAAGUCUGUGUCUGUGUCGCUCACUAGUAACCGUGAGUUUUUACCACUUCGUCACCUGUCGGCGGCGGCCGGGAGCAGGUUCCCGCAGGCGGCGCGGGGGGUCUUCCCCGCGCCCCGCCGCCGCCGGCCUCGCAGACCUGCCCUCCAGCCCCGCCCCGUUCUUGACCAAACAUGACAGACUCUGAACAUGCAGGGCACGACAGAGAAGAUGGCGAAUUAGAAGAUGGUGAAAUAGACGAUGCAGGAUUUGAAGAAAUACAAGAAAAAGAAGCAAAAGAGAAUGAAAAGCAGAAAAGUGAGAAAGCCUACAGAAAAUCAAGAAAAAAACAUAAGAAAGAGAGAGAGAAGAAAAAAUCCAAAAGGAGAAAACGUGAGAAACAUAAGCAUAAUUCCCCAUCUAGUGAUGAUAGUUCGGACUACAGCCUUGAUUCAGAUGUUGAACAUACAGAAAGUUCCCAUAAAAAAAGAACUGGUUUCUACAGGGAUUAUGACAUUCCAUUUACUCAGCGUGGACAUAUAUCAGGAAGCUACAUAACAUCAAAGAAGGGUCAACAUAACAAAAAAUUUAAAAGUAAAGAAUAUGAUGAGUACAGCACCUACAGUGAUGACAACUUCGGUAACUACAGUGAUGACAACUUUGGUAACUACGGUCAGGAAACAGAGGAAGAUUUUGCCAAUCAGCUGAAACAAUACAGGCAAGCUAAAGAAACCUCAAAUAUUGCUUUAGGGUCAUCAUUUUCUAAAGAAUCAGGAAAAAAACAGAGAAUGAAAGGAGUUCAGCAAGGUAUUGAACAGAGAGUUAAAAGUUUUAAUGUUGGUCGUGGACGUGGCUUGCCGAAGAAAAUCAAACGAAAAGAACGUGGGGGAAGAACCAAUAAAGGGCCUAAUGUGUUUUCAGUAUCGGAUGACUUUCAAGAGUAUAAUAAACCAGGGAAAAAAUGGAAGGUUAUGACUCAGGAAUUUAUUAAUCAGCACACAGUGGAACACAAAGGAAAACAAAUCUGUAAAUACUUCCUGGAAGGGAGGUGUAUUAAGGGAGAUCAGUGUAAAUUUGAUCAUGAUGCAGAGUUGGAGAAAAGAAAAGAGAUCUGCAAAUUUUAUUUACAAGGAUAUUGUACCAAAGGAGAGAACUGCAUUUAUAUGCAUAAUGAAUUUCCAUGCAAGUUCUAUCAUAGUGGAGCAAAAUGUUACCAGGGAGACAACUGUAAAUUUUCCCAUGAUGAUCUAACUAAAGAAACAAAGAAACUUUUGGACAAAGUGUUGAAUACUGAUGAAGAACUCAUAAAUGAAGAUGAAAGAGAAUUAGAGGAACUUAGAAAGCGUGGCAUAACUCCUCUUCCCAAACCACCUCCAGGGGUUGGGCUUCUGCCAACCCCUCCAGAGCAUUUUCCCUUUUCUGAUCCUGAAGACGAUUUUCAGACAGAUUUCUCUGAUGAUUUUAGGAAAAUUCCAUCUCUUUUUGAAAUAGUUGUAAAACCUACUGUGGAUUUAGCGCAUAAAAUUGGGAGGAAGCCACCAGCAUUUUAUACCAGUGCCUCACCACCAGGACCACAAUUUCAGGGAAGCAGUCCACACCCUCAACAUAUCUAUAGUUCUGGGUCAAGUCCAGGUCCUGGACCUAACAUGUCUCAGGGACACAGUAGUCCUGUGAUGCACCCAGGCUCCCCUGGACAUCACCCAUGUGCAGGACCUCCUGGUCUACCAGUGCCACAGAGCCCACCUUUACCACCUGGUCCACCUGAAAUUGUAGGUCCUCAAAAUCAAGCUGGAGUGCUUGUUCAACCAGACACAUCUUUGACACCACCAAGUAUGGGUGGGGCUUACCACUCCCCAGGCUUUCCAGGACAUGUGAUGAAAGUACCCAGAGAGAAUCACUGUUCUCCAGGUUCAUCAUACCAGCAAAGUCCUGGUGAAAUGCAGCUCAACACCAAUUAUGAGUCCCUGCAAAACCCAGCUGAGUUUUACGAUAAUUACUAUGCACAGCAUUCUAUACAUAAUUUUCAGCCACCCAAUAACUCUGGUGAUGGGAUGUGGCAUGGUGAAUUUGCCCAGCAGCAGCCUCCUGUUGUUCAAGACUCACCUAACCAUGGGAGUGGGUCUGAUGGCAGCAGCACUAGGACAGGCCAUGGCCCUCUGCCUGUACCAGGCCUCCUCCCUGCAGUGCAAAGAGCUCUUUUUGUAAGACUUACUCAGAGAUACCAAGAAGAUGAAGAACAAACCAGCACCCAACCUCAUAGGGCACCAAGCAAGGAAGAAGAUGAUACAGUUAACUGGUAUUCCAGUAGUGAAGAGGAAGAAGGAAGCAGUGUCAAAUCAAUACUGAAAACAUUACAGAAACAAACAGAAACUUUAAGGAAUCAGCAACAACCUUCCACAGAACUCAGCACUCCUACUGAUCCAAGACUUGCUAAAGAGAAAAGUAAAGGAAACCAAGUGGUUGACCCUAGGCUUAGGACUAUCCCAAGGCAAGACAUUAGAAAGCCUUCUGAGUCUGCCCCACUGGAUCUUAGACUUGCGUGGGAUCCCAGGAAAUUGAGAGGGAAUGGAAGUGGUCACAUAGGCUCUUCUGUUGGUGGAGCAAAGUUUGAUUUGCAUCAUGCAAAUGCUGGCACUAAUGUCAAACACAAAAGAGGCGAUGAUGAUGAUGAAGAUACAGAAAGAGAACUGAGAGAAAAAGCUUUCUUAAUACCUUUGGAUGCCUCACCUGGCAUAAUGCUCCAGGAUCCAAGGUCACAAUUGAGACAGUUCAGUCACAUUAAAAUGGACAUUACUCUAACCAAACCCAACUUUGCAAAACACAUCGUGUGGGCUCCCGAAGACUUACUUCCAGUACCUUUACCUAAACCUGAUCCAGUGUCUUCAAUCAAUUUACCUCUGCCCCCACUUAUAGCUGACCAGAGGCUAAAUAGAUUAUGGAAUACAAAAAGUGAUCUUCAUCAAAAUACAGUGUCCAUUGAUCCAAAAUUAGCAGCCAAAGCCAAAAUUAACACAACAAACAGAGAAGGCUACCUAGAACAAUUUGGAGACUCACACGGUUCAGGAGCUAAAUUAGGAGAUCCUAGACUACAAAAAAAUUUUGAUCCUAGGCUUCACAGACUGCCCAAUACAGAGUCUCAUCAAGUGGUUAUGAAGGAUUCACAUGCAUCAAAGGGUGCCCCUCACUUACCCAGAUCAAACCCUGGUUCAUCACAGCCCUCAGGGGCAGGAACUAGCAAUUCUGGUUCCGGGGCUCUGCCUCCAUAUGCCCCUAAACUCUCUUCCUCAGCUGGCCUUCCACUGGGAACUUCCACUUCAGUUCUUAGUGGUAUUAGUUUGUAUGACCCUAGGGAUCACGGUUCAUCAUCCACAUCAGAGCUAGCAACAGCUUCUUCAGGAGAAAACUCAAAGAACCAGAAAAAAAGUGGUGGCUUAAAAAGUAGUGACAAAACUGAACCUUCUCCUGGAGAAGCCAUCCUUCCACAAAAACCCAGUCCAAACGUGGGAGUCACUCUUGAGGGGCCAGCUGACCCACAGGCGGACGUUCCCAGGAGUUCUGGUAAGGUUCAGGUCCCAGCAGUGCACAGCCUUCCUGUUCAGGCAUUAACAGGCUUAAUUAGGCCACAGUACAGUGAUCCAAGGCAGGCAAGGCAGCCAGGACAGGGGAGCCCGACCCCAGAUAAUGAUCCCGGUAGAGAAACAGAUGACAAAUCUCUGAAAGAGGUUUUUAAAACUUUUGAUCCAACUGCUUCACCAUUUUGUUAGCUAUUGUGUAACUGAGCAAUUCUUUUCACUCUUGUGACUAUCUCAGUCCUCUGCUGUUUUGUAACUGGUUUACCUCUAUAGUUUAUUUAUUUUUAAAUUAUAAACACUUUUCAGCUGCUAGUAUCAGAACCACAUGAAGUUAUAGCCUCUAAAGCCUGUGGUAUUUUAUAUAAUAUUUUUAUAACUUUAAGAGACUGUAGUAAUUGACCUAAAAACUUAUGUUAGCUUCAGUAAAAGUACUUUUAUUGUAAAUAAACAAUCAUGAACUCAACACUCUGCCUGAAUAUAUGCCAGUUGUCUUUCAUAAUCAAUGUUUAGAUAAAUGAUUGCCACUUUUUAUAUGGUUGUUUAGUUUCAAGCAAUAUGAUGUACAUUACUUUUGAGAAACAGUAUUUUGACUAGGACCUCUCUUAUUUGUCAGCACAGAACUGAUUAAUAUGUAAUGCUACCUGCUAAUUAAAAUGUAAAAUCAAGUAAAGAAAACAUUUUAAAAUUACAAUUAGCAGAGCAGUUCAUGUUUAAGGGCAUCACUUUUAUUAGUAUUGGCAAUAUUAUUUGUGUAAAUGAAGCAUUUGAAUGUCAUAUCUUUUUAAAGUAUUUUAUUGUAUACUGUAUCAUAGAAGUUGGAGGUAUAUAAAUAGAACAUUUUGCUAAAGUGAAAAAUUUCCAAGUUCUCUAGCAUAACUUUUUACAUUUAAUUUUUCAUAUGAAAUAGCAAUUAGUUACUGCUGUGUUACAUUGUGAUGUUUAUGUAUGUCAAUGUUUUUGUCUUUAACAGCAUAAUUUAUAUUGCUUUUUCAAAUGAUGUAGCUGCAUUAAUUGUGUUCAUCAUGACUUUGGCGAUUUUUAACAAAAUUUUUAAAGACCCAGUGAGAGUCUGUAGUGAUUAUUACACGGAUAAUGUUUUAAAUGUCUAGGUUCUGUAUUUUUUUCUUAAAUAGCAAGAAAAUACAGAUUGCUAGUAUAGUCAACAGUAUUUGGCUAUCAAUAAAGAAUCUCUUUAAGAUCUCACCCGGCUGGCAUUCUGUAACAGAGGGGAUUACCUGGUGUUUUAAGUAUUUAAUGUCCUCAUAGUGUGGAAAUCCCCUAAAUUGAUUAGAAAUUGUAUUUUAUGAAAAAUAACUUGUAUUCAUUCUUGUGUAUUUAUUACAAUAUAUAAAUAAUGGCAACUCUUUGUUUUAUACAUAUAUAAUUUAUAACUGAAUCUAAGUAUUAGACUGCUACUCAUAUUUUGAACUGCAGGUGUAGGACAGUGUUUGCUGGUAACAACUCCAAUGUGUAUUAAUAACUUGAAAAGGAGCAUUUCACUAUAAAAGAUAAUGAAGUAGGUAAUGAAAUCAGUCCUUGAAUGAAAGCAGUGCCCUUGAGAAGGGAUUUUUUUUUAAAUAUACAGUAAAAUAUUUCGUGGGAACCUAACACUCACAUAGCAUAUGGUUUAUUAAUAAUGCAUAUCCUUUCUAAUCACUUCUUCAAUUCUUUUUGCUGCAGUUCUGUGCUAAAAUGGGGUUGUGGUUAAGUGAACGAGAACUCUGCCUACCUAAGAAGUUCAUUGUGUUCUAAGUGGAAGGAGAGUUACUGAAGGGAAUGUGAAUUUUUACCGUUUGUACUUAAGAUACAUUUGUUGUCUAAAAUGGCUCUGGAUAACAUUUUUGGGUUAAAAAAUGUAAUUUAAAGCCACCAUAGAAAGUAUUUUCUGAUUUACUGUCCAAAUGAAUUUUGUUGUUAAUUGAGAAGUCAAUAAAAUGGAUUAAACUGACAGAAAAAAAACAUAUAUAUAUAUCCCAAGGUGUAAUUUACUCUUUUGUCAGGAUAAAAUCAGAAAAAUGGCUGAUUUUAGUAAAUGAAAUUUUUAGCAAAUCUUUCAUUCAUGUAGUUUAUAAUUAUUGUGUCAAGCAGUGCUGUUUACAUUUUAAGCAUCAUACAAAAAAGAUAAUUUGGCUUGCUAAACAUCAAAAUAGAAUCCAAACUCUUAACCGAAUAUCUUUUUUACAACUAAAAGAGAUAUUCCAAGAUUUAUUAAAGAGUCAGGUUUAAAAGUUAUUAAUGCAAAUUAUGUAAUGUUCAUUUAUUCAGUAUUCUUGAGUCCCUGUUACCUCAAUUGGUGUUCUAGAGGCUAUUUUACAAGAAAGUUUGAACUUAGUUUCAAAUUUGACAAUAUAUUUUAUAUGAAAAUGUUUAUGUUUAAAAUAACUUAUUUAUUAUGCAGCAUUUUUAUUGUGAUAACGUUAGUUUAUGGGAUAUUCUGUCAUAUCCUGUAAACAUAGUUUAUUUUUCUUCUUUUUUCCCAUUUUCUCAUACAAAUUGAAUAAGUAGCCAUUUUCCCCCAAUGAAUACCUCUUCUUUUAGGUCAAUUGGUGUUUUUAGAAUCCAUGUAAUUUGAUUUGCACUGUUAGAUUGAAAAGUAAGUUACGUUCCUGUUCUUAGAAGCCACACAUUUAGAGAUAACAGAAAUAACUUGAGUCUUAAGAGUAUGGAUAGGCUCAUCCAAUGAGAUGUAACUUAGCUAUUCAUACUGUUUGUGAUGGAAAUUCUAUACCUGUUUACUGUGAUGAUGAAUACAGUGGAUAUAGCAGGGGGUUGAAAUGGAACACACAGAAGAUCAUGACAAUUGAGAUUCAGCAACUGCUGUCUCAUAUCUUGGUUAAGACCUCAUUGUGAACCUUGAACACAAAUCAGAUGUUGGAGUGAUUUCAAACUCUAUUUCAACAAUUGGGUCUGUUUCUAUAUGGACCCUCUAUUUCCCAGCUGAAUGUUUCAAACCCCCAAAUUAGGCUGCAACCGAAAGAGCCUAAUUGUGAAAUGAUGUGCGCUUAUGUUUCUGUUUAUCCUUUAGCCAUGGAACUUUAAAGAGUAGUGUUCCUCCUACUUACUUUAAGCUGGAAGAAGAGUUGAGUAGUAAAUCCUGUGUGAACUUUUAGCUCAGCUACUCUGCUGAAUUAAUUAGAGGUAGGAAGGACUUACAAGGGCUGGAAGUUUAAAGAGAAUAAAUUCAUAUUUUUUGUUCUGAAUUGAUUUCUGUGUAAUUUAUAUCAGUAUCUAGUUGCUUAUCUGUGAAAUUGGGUUAAUUUUUAUUGAUCACAUUUGAUGUAAAGAAUGAAUUAUUUUUGUAAAGUAUUUGUAAAUAUAAAAUUGCUUUAUAACUUGAAUGAACAUAAUCAUUAUGCUCCCAUUAGGGUGCAUUAAGUUGUACAAAUUCCAAAAUAACAUGGUAUGGUUUGUAUGGUUUAGCAAUUUUACGAAGCUUCAGAUGACAUGCACUGGUGACACAACAGUAGAAUUUCCUGAGAGGUUGAGUGAAUAUUAACCCAUCAAGUUAGCAAUUUCCUUAACUACAUGAGUAUCAGGAAGACAGGACUUCCCUGCCUUAGAGCUAUAUAGACUUGGGCCUCUUCAAGAUCUGACUUCUCUGCACAUUCUAUACAGGUUGGAUAUUGAUGGAGGGUUAAAAAUGCUAUGACAGUUCAUGGUGCAUGGUGUGUUUGUUUAAAUCAUAGCAUGUUUAGGCAAAGUGGCCAGCUCAUUCAAUAUAAGAGCCACCAGCUCUUAGAAACAACAGAUAUAUUCACACCCAGUCUGUAAUAUGUAUUUCUUCAGGCAUGUCACACUGCGGUCUUCCUGAAAGACUACUUACUUCAUAAAGGUAUUAUGUUUCUUUAAUUAAUGGCCACUAGAAGUUAGGAAGCUCCUAGGGACCAGGAUAUGAGAUCUUAAAGAGGCUGUCAGAAUCUCUUCAUUUGCAUGACAUAGAAUCUGUGGUGGAGAUGUUUUCCCUGAUGUUUUUGGAGGGUUGGACUGUGUUGAAGGCUGUACCUUGGUGGGGGUGGUCUGCAGUCAUGCAGUCCACUGAUAGGGUCCCCCACCCCGCAAGCUUCAAUAAUUGAGCUUUCUGUUAAUUUCUUGAAUUAUCUUUUCAAAAAUGGUUUGGCAGCACUUGAUGACAUUAUGUUCAAAAUUAAGUCCAGUAAAAUAUAUAAGCAUUUGUAAACUAUAAUUAUAGUUUAAAUAAGACUUAGUUUAGGAAAUCCAAGUUUUGACAUAUAUAACCAAACGGCCUAAGAGUUCAAAGCUAUUUUCUUAGGUGUUACACCUUAGCAUUUACAUAAUGCCUUCUCCCCAAGCAGUUUCAUGUGGUUUGCAGAAAGUUUUGGCAGCUACCAGUCACUAUAUUGCUGGAGUUUUGUGUUUGAGUAUGUCAUUUAUGUCAUUUAUCAGCAGUAUCUGCCAGUUGUGACAAAGCCCUCCCUAUUAUCCUGCCUUUCCUGGAAAGGAUACAGACCCAAGAAAAGUUAACAUCUACAUAGUACUUAGAAUUUCUAAUUUUAAAAUAAGAAACAAAAAGCACAUUUAAAAUAAUAUUUUAUGCUUUUGGAGACAGGACCCACAUGUAUCUCCUUAUUUUUAUACUUGCCAUAGAAACAAGCCUAGUUGUAGGCCUACAGUGGGUGCUUUGUUAACUGCUUGUUGAUGGCUUCCUGACAUCCAUCCAAAUGUCACUUUUACAGAUGCUGUCACCCGUUAAACAGGUGUGGCAGAAGUAUUCCAUGACUGCAUUAGGAAGAAUGCACCUUAUGGGUUAUAUCUCUUUUGGUAGACAGCCCACCUGCUCUUUUUUGUCCCCACCCUCAGCCCAAGCAAUGUGAAGACAGAUUAUGGCAACUUAGGAGCUCCAUGUUUCCAUAAUAAUUCAUAACUUUAAGAGUCCUCCAGACUUACAAGAUUACUUCAUGGUGAAAGUUUGGAUUGAUCAAUAAUUUAUUCCUAUAAAGGUCUGCAGGAUUUUUUCUGUAACCAGAAAAGUAACUGCAUAGCCAUUCUUUUUUUUUUUUUUUAAUUUGUUGUUGUUUUUGUUUGAGACAGAGUCUUCAUUCUUGUUGCCCAGGCUGGAGUGUAAUGGUGCAAUCUCGGAUCACUGCAACCUCUGCCUCCCAGGUUCAAGUGAUUCUCCUGCCUCAGACUCCCAAGUAGCUGGGCUUACAGGCACGUGCCACCACACCCAGCUAAUUUAUUGUAUUUACUAGAGACGGGGUUUCACCAUGUUGAUCAGGCUGAUCUUGAACUCCUGACCCCAGGUGAUCCACCCGCCUCAACCUCCAAAAGUGUUGGGGUUACAGGCGUGAGCCACCGUGCUCAGCCUGUUUUUUAUUUAUUUUUUUGAGACAGUCUCACUUUGUCGCUCAGGCUGAAGUGCAGUGGCGCUAUCAGCUCACAGCAGCCUCCGCCUCCCAGGUUCAAGCAAUUCUCCCACCUUAGCUUCCUGAGUAGCUGGAACUACAGGUGUGUGCCACCACACCCAGCUAAUUUUUGUAUUUUUUUGGUAGAGACAGGGUUUGACCAUGUUGGCCAAGCUGAUCUUGAACUCCUGGCCUCAAGUGAUCCACCAGUCUUGGCCUCUCAAAGUGCUGGGAUCACAGGCAUGAGCCACCACGCCUGGCCCAGUCUUUUUUUUUAAUUAUUAUUUAUUUUUAUUUAUUUAUUUUUUGAGACGGAGUCUUGCUCUGUUGCCCAGGCUGGAGUGUAGUGGCAUGAUCUUGGCUCACUGCAACCUCUGCCUCUGGGUUCAAGCAAUUCUCCUGCCUCAGCCUUCUGAGUAGCUGGGAUUAUAGGCAUGCGCCACCACAACCAGCUAAUUUUUUAUAUUUUUGGUAGAGACACAGUUUCAUCAUGUUGGCCCGGCUGGUCUCAAACUCCUUACCUCAAGUGAUCUGCCCGCCUCAGCCUCCCAAAGUGCUGGGAUUACAGGCGUGAGCCACUGUGCCUGGCCAGUCUUUUAUUUUAAAAUAAAUACUUAGUCCUAACCUAGUGAAUUAUCAAUAGCAUUUAAAAUUCCUUCUAUCCUGAUACCAUGAACAGUAAUUUUCCCUUUUAAGUUAUGAUUUGACUCUAAUUUUGGGUCUUGUAUCUGGUCUUUAAACACCUUUCGUUACCCUUUGGAAUAGAACAAUCAUGCUACUGUUAGCAAAAUUAUUGUAGGCAUAAGGAAGAGCUGUGAGUUCAAAGAAGAUUGUGAGUUCUUGGAAUAGUAUUUUACAGCGUUGUUUAUUCUUGACCUUCUUGUUUUUUAAGCUUAGAGUUUAUAAGAAAAAAGUGAAUAUAUAGCUAAUUAUAGCAUUUUAGAAAAAAUUAGCUCUGCAGAUAGUCAGGCCCCAUACUUCUUGGCUCAUUACUGAUUUUAAUACCUUCAUGAGAGUAUUAAGGUUGAAAGGAAUGGUGAAAUUUGCAUUAUCAGAGGUCUGAUAUGUAAUUUAUUGUAAAGAAAUUAAAUAUAUAGAGGCUCAAUUAAAAAAUAACCAUAUUCUCAAACCUCCAUUACCACUAAUAUCUUGGGGUUGUCAAUGAUAGACUAUAUAUAUAUGUAUGUAUAUGUGUGUAUAUAUAUAUAUAUAUAUAUAUAUAUAUAUAUAUAUAUAUAUAUAUAUAUAUAUAUAAUUUUUUUUUUUUGAGACGGAGUCUUGCUCUGUCACCCAGGCUGGAGUACAGCUCACAGCAACCUCUGCCUCCCAGGUUCAAGCAAUUCUGCCUCAGCCUCCCGAGUAGCUGGAAUUACAGACGCCUGCCACCACACCCAGCUAAUUUUUCGUAUUUUUUAGUAGAGAUGGGGUUUCACCAUGUUGGCCAGGCUGAUUUCGAACUCCUGACCUCAAAUGAUCCACCGACCUGAGCCUCCCAAAGUGCUGGCCUUACAGGCAUGAGCCACCACACCUGGCCUAGACUAUACCUUUUAUACACUUUUUAAAUAGAGAAAGUGAAAAAUGAUAAACUAACCAUUAUAAAAUAGAGGUUUGAGUCCACCUGUAUUUUACAGAAAUUUGCCCUCAAAUGUUUGAGAGGGAAGUCACAUAUGAUAGAAAAAUAUCUUUUCAAGGGUAGAAUGAUAUUUCCUUAUAAAAGUGACAAUCAAAAAAGACUCAUUUGUAUACUUGCCAAAGUUUAAAAGUUUUUUACAUUCCUUACCCUAAACCCACUGCCCCAUCCACCCAGAAUUCAGAAAGGGUUUGGCAUAGAUCCAGGGCUCCAGGGCCCAGGUCAUUUUGUUAUUAGUCUAGGGCUUUUGUCCUCCACAGUCUAGGCAGGGCAUCUUUGUAUGUGUGUUGCUGGUUGGGGCCAGGGACGGGGGCAGGCGGGAGUUGUCCAGGUUUAAGAUUGUUUGUUUUCCAUCAGAUCCACAAGCAAUAUCUGUGGGCUGAAAUCCAGGUUAUACCUAUUCACUAUGACUUUUUUUUUUUUUAACUUUCUACUGUAAUUAUUUCAGUUCCCCGAAGUUGUAUCUCAAAUGUUGGGGAAAUGCUGCCUUGACUAUUUUACUUUGGAAGGUUUUACUAGAUAUCAGUUUAGUAGAUUAAUGACGUUGUUAAUCUGUCUGCUCAAAAGACACCAGCAAGGGGGUAUACUUUGCUGAACUGAUAAAUUAUUCUAUUAAGGACUAACCCAGUACUUGGCAAAAUUAGGAAUAACUUUUCCCCUCCUUCUUUACUAAUAAAUUUUCCAAGUUGCAUACUGUUGUUGCAAGUUUCUGUAAUUUUUUUCUGUAUACCUUUCUAUUGUCUGAAUUUAAAUAAAAAUGUUUCUAAUAA